CUCUGUGAGCCGCAACCUUUCCAAGGGAGUGGUUGUGUGAUCGCCAUCUUAGGGAGUGAGUGUGGCCGGGCCUUCUCCUGUGGCGGGUGUGGGGAGCGGAGCCCAGAGCUCCUGUGGGGCCGCUGCUUUGGCGGUGGGCCCAGCCGGGAGCAGCCUCUUUCGAAGGCCGCCGUGACCUCUUCAAGGGCGUGGAGACGGGAAGGAAAAGGCCCCGGUUGGGGUUCCAGGGCGCCGGUAACGUUAACCGGCGCCUUGCCUGUCCUCUAACCGUCGCUCCCUCCUCCCCUAGAAAGAUGUUCUCGUCCGUGGCGCACCUGGCGCGGGCGAACCCCUUCAACACGCCACAUCUGCAGCUGGUGCACGAUGGUCUCGGGGACCUCCGCAGCAGCUCCCCAGGGCCCACGGGCCAGCCCCGCCGCCCUCGCAACCUGGCAGCCGCCGCCGUGGAAGAGUACAGUUGUGAAUUUGGCUCCGCGAAGUAUUAUGCACUGUGUGGCUUUGGUGGGGUCUUAAGUUGUGGUCUGACACACACUGCUGUGGUUCCCCUGGAUUUAGUGAAAUGCCGUAUGCAGGUGGACCCCCAAAAGUACAAGGGCAUAUUUAACGGAUUCUCAGUUACACUUAAAGAGGAUGGUGUUCGUGGUUUGGCUAAAGGAUGGGCUCCGACUUUCCUUGGCUACUCCAUGCAGGGACUCUGCAAGUUUGGCUUUUAUGAAGUCUUUAAAGUCUUGUAUAGCAAUAUGCUUGGAGAGGAGAAUACUUAUCUCUGGCGCACAUCACUAUAUUUGGCUGCCUCUGCCAGUGCUGAAUUCUUUGCUGACAUUGCCCUGGCUCCUAUGGAAGCUGCUAAGGUUCGAAUUCAAACCCAGCCAGGUUAUGCCAACACUUUGAGGGAUGCAGCUCCCAAAAUGUAUAAGGAAGAAGGCCUAAAAGCAUUCUACAAGGGGGUUGCUCCUCUCUGGAUGAGACAGAUACCAUACACCAUGAUGAAGUUCGCCUGCUUUGAACGUACUGUUGAAGCACUGUACAAGUUUGUGGUUCCUAAGCCCCGCAGUGAAUGUUCAAAGCCAGAGCAGCUGGUUGUAACAUUUGUAGCAGGUUACAUAGCUGGAGUCUUUUGUGCAAUUGUUUCUCACCCUGCUGAUUCUGUGGUAUCUGUGUUGAAUAAAGAAAAAGGUAGCAGUGCUUCUCUGGUCCUCAAGAGACUUGGAUUUAAAGGUGUAUGGAAGGGACUGUUUGCCCGUAUCAUCAUGAUUGGUACCCUGACUGCACUACAGUGGUUUAUCUAUGACUCCGUGAAGGUCUACUUCAGACUUCCUCGCCCUCCUCCACCCGAGAUGCCAGAGUCUCUGAAGAAGAAGCUUGGGUUAACUCAGUAGUUAGAUCAAAGCAAAUGUGGACUGAAUCUGCUUGUUGAUCAGUGUUGAAGAAAGUGCAAAAGGAACUUUUAUAUAUUUGACAGUGUAGGAAAUUGUCUAUUCCUGAUAUAAUUACUGUAGUACUCUUGCUUAAGGCAAGAGUUUCAGAUUUACUGUUGAAAUAAACCCAACUCUUCAUGAUUUGCCUGUGACUUAUUUUUAAAACUUUUUUAAAAAAGAUUUAGCUUUAAAAUAGUUGGAAAGAAUGAAGUAUAUAAGUUAAGGAAAAAAUACAAAACUGACCAUGACCAUUGUUGGUUGAAUAUUCCAGUUGCUAUUCAGAAAUUGUCAUAUGUCUCAAGUUUUAUCACACAAAGUUCCUGUAUUUCUAGGGAAGCAGACUUUAAAUUUCUAAAAACUUGAUUUAAUUAUAGUUAAAUAUGUGUAGUCAUUUGUGGUUAUUUUGGCAAGUAAAUGUCAGUGUAUACUUACAUUUUUGCAGCAUGUACUACACCUUUUUUAUGUUGGUGAGUUUGCUAAUCCUUAUUUGUAAGACAAGGUAAACCAAAUUAGGCUGAUUCUUAGAAUGACAGUAAAGGACCAAAGUGAUUGACAGCUGAAAACAAUUUUCAGGUACACUAAUUCUCUUUACACAGAUCUGACUUUUUUUUUUUUUGAGACGGAGUUUCACUCUUGUUGCCCAGACGAGUGUAGUGUCGCGAUCUCGCCUCACGGCAACCUCUGCCUCCCAGGUUCAAGCGAUUGUUCUGCCUCAGCCUCCCAAGUAGCUGGGAUUUCAGGCAUGUGCCACCACGCCCAGCUAAUUUUGUAUUUUUAGUAGAGACGGGGUUUCCCUGUGUUGGUCAGGCUGGUCUCGAACUUCCAACCUCAGGUGAUCCGCCCGCCUCAGCCUCCCAAACUGCUGGGAUUAUAGGCAUGAGCCACCGUGCCCGGCUCUGACUUUUUACAGAAAAUUGAACUAUUUUCAGUCUGGUAUUUUAAGAAAGGUACUGCUUGACAGCUGAACUAUAUGAAUGCCACUGGGGAAAAAGCAUUCCAUCAUACUUAGAUACGAGAUUGGAUUGUAGGUUUAAGCCCAUUUUUAAAGAGCUCCUAGAAAGUGAAUUAGUUUUUGUGUUUAGAUUCCCCUUAAGUUUGAUUAGGAAGUGUAUAAAAGUUCAAUCUUUUGUAAUGACAGCCCACCACUGGAAAAAAAACGAAAAACCUAGUGUAAUAUAUAACAUGCUGUUUUUCAAACACUAGAUUUUACCUAGAGUCCUUAUGUGUAAUACGUGGGUUGGUUAACAGUCCCUACGUAAAGCGUACAGAUGGCCUGGAGAGAAAAACUUUUUCAGAGAUUGGAGAGAAAUGUUACUACAAACUCAUGGUAAGGUCAGUGAACUCAAUUUAGAAGCCAGUGCAGCUAGUUGCAUGUUAACUUCUUUAUAUCAUCAUUGCCUGAACUUGUUAAAGGUUCCAACAUUUUACCUGUGCUGCAGGAAAAAAGGAAAAGUUGUAGGUACAAAUUUGGACCAAACUUUAAAAAGGUAAAGUAGGAUGUCUUCUGAACCCAACCAAGUGGUGGCUGUGGUGCUUAGCAGUAUCAACUGUAUAUUAUUUCUUGCUAUGUUAGCAAAGCAUCCAAAGAUCAAUGGUGUAUGAUAAGCUUUUCUGUGGGUGAAGAACUCGGGAGUAUCAGACUCUUCUGGUUCUGAGUCUCAUGAAGCUUUUCACUUCUGAGCUGAAAGGAUGCUCUUUGUGCUUUUCACUAUUAGUGGUAUAGUCUUUCCCGAAAAUCUCUAGCAUGGUGGCUUCAGGGCAGCUGGACUUAGGUGGUAUUUUGGGGCUCCAGGAGAGCUUGGCAGAGUUGGCUUUUUAGGACUUAUCCUUCAAUGUCACAUAACAUCACUUUUACCAUGCUCUUGGUUACAACAGUGAUGUCUCAGAAACCAAGUCCCAGAUUGAGGAAAAAAGGAACAUAGUCUCUACCUCUUCCUGAGAGGAAAGUCAGUCAACGUGUAAGAGGAGCAGUAGAAACGCAUUAGUCCAGCCAACGUGAAAGUGGACCGUAGAUCUAAAACAUUUUGGGUAUGCAGUUCAGCCAGCCCUUACUGAGGCAGUUCUGCCAAUCAGGAUUCAAGUUUUAUUUCCUAAGAGUUAUAAUAGGUUUUAUUUGUGGGCAUUGAUACAAAAUACGCUGUGUUCAAGCUAUGGAGCCUGCCACUGUAGUUACUAGAGUUACGGUUCAAAGCUAUUUCUGAGAGAAAGCCACUUCAUCCUCAAAACCCAAGAGGCCCACUUAAAGUGAUGCGAAUUCUCAUUUCAGGUUUUUAAAUUAUACUAAAAGAUUCUAGUAAGAAAAUUUUAAUAUGUAUGUAUUGGUGUUCUUUUUACAUUUCAUUUAAUGAAAUGUCUACUGUCAAUACGAUAAAGCAGAACCCAGUGGAGUAAGAAUACACGAAACUGCCAGGCACAGUGGGUCAUGCCUGUAAACCCAGCAUUCUGGGAGGCCGAGGCGGGUGGAUCACCUGAGGUCGGGAGUUCAAGACCAGCCUGACCAACAUGGAGAAACCCUGUCUCUACUAAAAAUACAAAAUUAGCUGCGGUGGUGGUGCGUGCCUGUAAUCCCAGCUACUCAGGAGGCUGAGGCAGGAGAAUCGCUUGAACCCGGGAGGCGGAGGUUGUGGUGAGCCAAGAUUGCGCCAUUGCACUCCAGCCUGGGCAACAACAGCGAAACUCUGUCUCAAAAAAAAAAAAUAUAUAUAUAUAUAUAUAUAUAUGAAGCUGAUAGUUGAAUUAUGUUGAUUCAGGGACAAGAUAGCAUUGCAUAGUAACUUCCAGUAGGAUCAAAUAUUUUGAGAGUGGUUAAAACGCCAAGGAAUCCUGAUUUUAUGAAAUUAUGCCUUCUGAUAGGUGCAACAAAAUUGAACAGAAGAGUAACAGCUUAACUAAACCUCCAUUGUGUGAAAGUUUUAUGAAAUGUUUUGACUUUUUUUUUUUUUUCCCUAGAGAACAGGGUUCUUGCUUUGUCGCCCAGGCUGGAGUACAGCCUUGAACUCCUGGGCUCAAGCGAUCCUCCUGCCUCAGCCUCCCAGUUAGCUGACACAAUUGGGAUGUGCCACUACUUGCUCCUGUUUUUUCAUAGACGGGUCCUGCUGUUGCUCAGGCUGGUCUCGGAUUCCUGGCCUCAAGCAACUUUCCUGCCCCAGCUCCUAAAGCGGCCAGGGUUACAGGUAGCCGCCUUGUCUGUCCCGUUUCGACCAUAUUUUAUUUUUGAGAAGGUCUUGCUCUGUCGCCAGACUGGAGUGCAGUGGCACGAUGAUAGCUCACUGCAGCCUCGAUCUCCCAAGCUCAAGUGAUCCUCCCACCUCAGCCUCUUGAAUAACUGGGACUGCAAGUGUGGACCACCAUGUCUGGCUAAUGUUUUUUAUUUUUAGCAGAAAUGAGGUCUUGCUAUGUUGCCAAGGCUAGUCUUGAACUCCUGAGCUCAAGCGAGCCUUCUGCCUUGGCCUUCCAAAGGGCUGGGAUUAGAGGGCUGAGCCACCACACUUGGCCAACCAUAUUUUAUUUUUUAUAUUUUUAUUUUAUUUGAUCCUUGUUCUGAAACCAUAAAGUGAGUUUAACAUUUCUGGCUGGGCACAGUGGCUCAUGCCUGUAAUUCUAACACUUUAGGAGACCAAGGCAGGAGGAUGCCUUGAGCCCAGGAGUUUGAGACCAUCCUGGACAACAUAAUGAGAAAAGAAAAUACAAAAAUUAAGGGGUGUGGUGACACAUGCCUGUAGUCUCAACUAUUUGGGAGGCUGAGGCAGGAGGAUUGCUUGAGCCCGAGAGGUUGAGGCUACAGUGAGCCAUGUUUACGCCAUUGCAGUCCAGCCUGGGCGACAGAGUGAAACCCUGUCUCAAAAAAAAAGUAACAUUUCUAUAUGAUUUUUGGGAUCGACAUGUCCAUAAUGUUAAUGAAGCGCAUAGCAGUCACUAGUAAAUUAGGAGUUAUACAUUGCUUCUAUAGCAUCAGAAAUUGUAUAUCAGGCCAGGUGCAAAAGCUCACUCCUGAAAUCCAAGCACUUUGGGAGGCUGAGGUGGGCGGAUUGCUUGAGGUCAGGAGUUCAAGAACAGCCUGGCCAACAUGAUGAAACCCCAGGUCUCUACUAAAAAUACAAAAAUUGGUCAGGCAUGGUGGUGCAUGCCUGUAAUUCCAGCUACUCGGGAGGCUGAGGCAGGAGAAUUGCUUGAACCCGGGAGGCAGAGGUUGCAGUGAGCCAAGAUUGUGCCACUGCACUCCAGCCUGGGCGACAGAGCCAGACUGUCUGAGGAAGAAAUUGUAUAUCAGGCUGGGCACAGUGGCUCAUACCCGUAAUCCCAGCACUUUGGGAGGCCCAGGCUGGGUAUCACUUGAGCCCAGGAGUUGGAGACCAGCCUGGGCAACAAAGUGAGACCCCUCUCUCUACAAAAAAUAAAUUAGCCAGGCAUGGUGGCACGUGCCUGUAAUCUCAGCUACUUAGGAAGCUGAAGGAGGAUCGUCUGAGCCCAGGAGUUUGAGGCUGCAAUGAGCUACAAUCACACCCCUGCACUCCGGCCUGGGCGACAGAGUGAUAACCUGUCUAAAAAAAUAAAAAUAAAUUGUAUAAUCAUAUUGCAAUUUUCUUUGCAUUACUGAUGAGGAAAAAUCUCAAAGUAAUUGUAAAAAAUCCUGGAUAUCACAUAGUUGAGAAACAAAGUUAUUUUAAACUUACAGGACUCUGUAGUUCACAGUUGAACACUGUGGCUUCCUGAAAUAUCAAAGAAUAAUGUACAUUAAUAAGCCAGCUACUAUCGGCAUCUUGUAAAAAUUAAAAAAUUAAACAUAAAUAAAAGUUCAAA